ACUCGCGCUGCCUCCGUGGUCCCUGCCUGGCUGAGGUGGCAGCAGGGGGCGGGACGCGCAGCGCUAUGGCAGAGGGCAGCGGGGAAGUGGUCGCAGUGUCUGCGACCGGGGCUGCCAACGGCCUCAACAAUGGGGCAGGCGGGACCUCGGCGACGACCUGCAACCCGCUGUCGCGCAAGCUGCAUAAGAUCCUGGAGACGCGGCUGGACAACGACAAGGAGAUGUUAGAAGCUCUCAAGGCACUUUCAACCUUUUUUGUUGAAAAUAGUCUGCGGACUCGAAGAAAUUUACGUGGAGAUAUUGAACGUAAAAGUUUAGCCAUCAAUGAAGAAUUUGUAAGCAUUUUCAAGGAAGUGAAGGAGGAACUUGAAAGCAUAAGCGAAGAUGUUCAAGCAAUGAGCAACUGUUGUCAAGAUAUGACAAGUCGCCUACAGGCAGCAAAGGAACAGACUCAAGAUUUAAUAGUAAAAACCACUAAGCUUCAAUCUGAAAGCCAAAAAUUAGAGAUAAGAGCUCAAGUUGCAGAUGCCUUCUUAUCCAAGUUCCAACUGACUUCUGAUGAAAUGAGUCUUCUCCGAGGUACAAGAGAAGGACCCAUUACUGAGGAUUUUUUCAAGGCACUGGGAAGAGUAAAACAGAUUCAUAAUGAUGUCAAAGUUCUCUUGCGUACAAAUCAACAAACGGCAGGUUUAGAAAUUAUGGAACAGAUGGCCUUACUUCAAGAAACGGCUUAUGAAAGACUUUACCGAUGGGCUCAAAGUGAAUGCAGAACAUUGACACAAGAAUCAUGUGACGUAUCUCCAGUAUUGACACAGGCAAUGGAAGCCCUGCAGGACAGACCUGUCUUAUAUAAAUAUACCUUAGAUGAAUUUGGAACAGCCAGAAGAAGUACAGUUGUUCGUGGAUUUAUUGAUGCGCUCACAAGAGGGGGCCCCGGAGGUACACCUAGACCAAUUGAAAUGCAUUCUCAUGACCCUUUGAGGUAUGUAGGAGAUAUGUUGGCUUGGCUCCAUCAAGCUACUGCUUCUGAAAAGGAACACCUUGAAGCUCUCUUAAAGCAUGUAACUACACAAGGUGUUGAAGAAAAUAUUCAAGAAGUUGUUGGGCAUAUCACUGAAGGUGUGUGCAGGCCUCUAAAGGUUCGAAUUGAGCAAGUAAUAGUUGCUGAACCUGGGGCAGUUUUAUUAUAUAAAAUUUCUAAUCUCCUCAAAUUUUAUCACCAUACAAUCAGUGGUAUUGUUGGAAAUAGUGCAACUGCAUUAUUGACUACCAUUGAAGAAAUGCAUUUGCUAAGCAAAAAAAUAUUCUUCAAUAGCUUGAGUCUUCAUGCAAGUAAAUUAAUGGACAAGGUUGAACUCCCACCACCUGAUCUUGGACCAAGUUCUGCACUAAAUCAGACACUCAUGUUGCUGCGUGAAGUUUUAGCAUCUCACGAUUCUUCAGUUGUACCAUUAGAUGCUCGUCAAGCUGAUUUUGUGCAGGUUUUAUCAUGUGUCUUGGAUCCUCUCCUACAGAUGUGUACUGUAUCAGCCAGCAAUUUAGGCACAGCUGACAUGGCCACUUUCAUGGUCAAUUCACUAUAUAUGAUGAAGACAACAUUAGCUCUAUUUGAAUUCACUGACAGACGUCUGGAAAUGCUACAGUUUCAGAUCGAAGCACAUUUGGACACACUUAUAAAUGAGCAAGCCUCUUAUGUUUUAACUAGGGUAGGCUUGAGUUACAUCUAUAACACUGUACAGCAACAUAAACCUGAACAGGGCUCUUUAGCUAAUAUGCCCAACCUAGAUUCUGUGACACUGAAGGCUGCAAUGGUUCAGUUUGAUCGUUAUCUGUCAGCCCCAGACAACCUAUUGAUACCACAGCUGAACUUUCUUCUAAGUGCCACAGUGAAGCGUCCACCCAACGGCCCAUGAUCAUCUUGUAACCAGUGCAGGACCUUGUGCUUCUGGAGCCAUUCCAGUUGUGGGAGGUGAUGUCUCGGAAAACUCUGCCUUGGGGACUGGCUAUAGAAAUGUGGCCAGAUGGCUUUGUCAUCUUCCCCUGUCUACUCUGUGACUCUUCAUCUGGUGGAAAUGCUGUGAGGGAUGAACCAAAUGGAAACUCAGAUUUACUCUUCAGAAUAAUGCGGAUCAUAAUACGCACACACACAGCAUGUAGAGUUGCUGUGUGGCUUAAAUAAGUAAAUGUAUGCAAAGCACUAAAAUGGUGUCUGUCUAAGUGUAAACACCAAUUGUGUUGGCUAUUAUCACUAUUGUUGUUCUUAUCUCAAAUAUGUGUUACUUUCUAAAUAACUUUAGUGUUCAUAGAUUGUUAAAAGACAAGAUGACCUGAAGAAAAGUAAGCCCUAAAAAUCCAUUAUUAACUUUUUUCUCCACCACUCUUUUCUUCUAAACUUCACUAUUCUUUGUGUUUUCACAAAAGUUGCUUACUUCACCUGGCAGAGAUAGCAUUACGCAGGGGAUGAUUAAAAUAUACUCACUUGUACUUGUUGGUUUUAAAUUUUAUUAUUUAUGAAUAGGUAAUAGCAUGUACACUGUAAAAAUCUCAAAAGGCAAAAAAGGAUAUACAGUAAACAUUAAGUUCCUCUUACCCUGGACCUUAGCCAUCAAGUUCUCUUCCCCAUAGGCAAUCCCUGUUGCCUAAUUUCCAAUUCCCCUGCAUACUUUAAAGAUCAUCUGUGCAUCUGCACUCAGACCACUCACACGUCUAAAACAAAUGAUAGCACACUACACACAAAGUUCUGUUCCUUUUUAUGCUCAAUGAUAUGUUUUGCAUCAUAUUUCACUGCCGUAUAAAUAAUGCUGCCUCGAUUUUUAAAAUAACUGAACAGUAAUACACAGUAUGAAUUUACUCCAAUUUAUAAUCCAAUCCUUAGUUAAUGGAUAUUUUGAUUUUGUUGUUAAGAAUCAUGCAGCAAUGAUGUACCUGUUAGACAUGAGUUAUUAAUUUCUCUUCGAAGAAUCAAUAUGUCACUACGUUCAAUUCUUUGCCUUCUACUUUUAAACUUCACUUCCUCAUAAAGCAACCUUUUGCGAUCAUCUGCUCCACCCUGACUCAUUCCAAUCACCUGCUCCACCCUGACUCAUUCUGAUCACCUGCUCUGCCCAGACUCAUUCCCAUCACCUGCUCCACCCUGACUUAUUCCAAUUACCUGCUCCACCCUGUCUCAUUCUCCACCCUGACUCAUUCCAUAACCAUUUUUCCCACCAAACCAGUCACCCCCUCACCCUCUUUAAAUUAGCUAAUCGGAAUUAGUUUAGCUUGUGUGGUCUAACCUAGCCAAUAGAUGAAUGACACAGCAGCAGGAGCCACGUUCGUCAGGGAUAAGAACACCUUCCCCUUCCUUGUCCAGGGGUGUACUCACCAUUGCUCCAUCUGUGAGGGCGCACCCUUCUAUAGAAGUAAAUUGCCUUGCUGAGAAGAAAAAAAGAAAAUUUUAUAUUUGAGUGCUAUUUAUUUUGUGGCACCAAAACUAUUUAUAACAUACCUGAUCUUUAUUUUAAAUUUUUGUUUAUUUAAAUAUUAAAUAUAUUAUCCACCUGGUAUUAAUUUGUUUAAAUAAAUGUGAGGUAGGGUUCCAUUGCUAUUUUUUAACCAGGUAGGUUAUAUUGACUAACCUUCACUUUGAAAGUGAUUUGAAAUACACUUUUCAUUUAUUAAAUUCUCCCUUGUGUUUAGGCAGUAAGGCAUAAUAUUUGAGAGUGUGGGCUCUGCAGUCCAGCUAUCUGGGUUUGAAGUUUAUCUCCUUUAUUUGCGAGUGGUACAAACUUGAACAAAUUAUGUAAUUUGUUUUUCUCAAUUCCCUCAUGCACUAAGUGAGGAUAAAAAUAGCAAUAACACCAUGAGAUUGCUGAUAACAAAAUGCAAGGUAAAAAUUGUGUAAGGCUUAAAAUUGUGUAGCCUGGUAUACAAGAGGCUCUAAAUAACAUAAGCUAUUAUUGCUUUUCUACUUAUUAUUAUUUCUGGCUUUUGUAGUCUUUUUCCCAUUGUUGAUCUUUCUACUAUUCACAAAGCAUGAGUCUAGUAUCUGUAGAUUUAUAAACUAAUUAAUGUAACUUUUCAAUAUGUUUUAAUAUCUCAUAGAUACUGUUCUUCCUCAUUACUUUUCUAUUUUAUAAAUUUCUAUUUCAUCUGCUUCAUAAAUUUUGCAUUCUCAUAAACUAAGAAUCAUCUCCUGUAGUUAAAAAAUAUUGUUUGUAUUUUUGUUGGGAGUAGAGUGAAUUAAAAUAUAUUGACUUAAGGAGAACUGACAUCUUUAUAAUAUUGAAUCUUCCUGUUUGAGAUUGGACUUUAUGUCCAUAUUUUAAAGUCUUUGUUUAUGACCCUAAGUAUAAUUUUAACGUUUUUAUAUUAGGCUUAUUUCUAGAUACUUUUUGUUAAUAUAUCAUCUAACUGGUUGUUCUUCAUAUAUAUAAUGACUAUGAAUUUUUUCUCAGUCUUUUUUCUGAAUUCUCACAUCAUUUGUGUUAUAUUUUUAAGUUGAUUCUCUUGAGUUUUUCAGGUAAACAAUUAUAUCACCUAUAAAAAUAAUGUUGCCACCUUAAAUUAAGAAAAUGUUUUUCUAUUGUCUAAUUGCAUGGACUGUUGCCUCAGGAACAGUAUAAGAUUGCUUACAAAAGCCUUGCUUUCUUGUUCCAGAUUUUAAAAACAAGGCUUUCAAUGACAAUCUCGCUAGCAAGAAGCUGGUAUACUUACAUACAUACAUACAAACAGACAGACACCCACUUUCUAUAUGUAUAUCUAGAUAGAUUUAGAUAGACAUAUAUGUGUGAUUCCUGUUAAGAUGAAUCUAUUUUUGGUAUUUAAGAUUUUAAAAAUCUAGAAUGGGUAUUAUUAUAUUGUAUUGAAGCUCUUAAGCAUCUAUGGAAAUGAAAGUAUGAUUCUUCUCUUUCGACUAAUUAAUAUGUGAUCCAUAGUAUUUUAGUAACAGAUUUCCUAAUAUCGAAUGAUCUAGGCAUUGAUUCUAGCAGAUUAUGUCUAUGGGUAUUUUAUUUAAGAUUUUGCAUCAGUAUUAAUAAAUGACCAUGGUCUAUGGGUUUGCUUUUUUGUGUGCUAUGUUUGCAGAGUGUUUGUAGUUUACAAGAGAUUUUUGCAAACUUCUAUUUAUGACAAUAUGGUAGAUUAUAUAUCUGAAAAAAAAACCUUCUCAUUACAGAACAUAUACAAAACUGCUGAAUAAAACGAGGCAACCAACAUUUUAAAUAUAUGGUUAAUAAGGUUUUA